AUGAAUACAAAAAGCAUAGGCGGACCAUGAUAAUUUCCCCAGAGCGUCUUGAUCCUUUUGCAGAUGGUAGAAGGACAAGAAAAAAAUGAGCCAAUGCCAUAGAAACGCAAAGGGUUAAAGGUUUUACUUUUACUUUUGUUUUGGGUACGCUUUCUAUACUUGGAUCAAAUGUAUUUUUCUGCUCAAAAUACUUUCAAAUUAUUGAAAGUUUUCAUUCCAAAUCCUAGAUUUUUAGGAUUGUUACCCUUGAGAAACUGUUUCUCACACUAGAGCUCCCCCCAUAGUGCUCUAAAUAUAGCUUAGUAAAGGCACCUACUUUGCUCUAAGCAUACUUAAAGUUAAAACAAAAGUAUGUAUACGAAGAGUUUGAUAUUUUUAAUAGUUGGAGUCUGUUUUGCUAAUUUUAGUGUGCAAGUCAGCACAAGGGGCAUAGUGAGCCUGAUGGAAGCUUUCCUCAGGUGAGUGAGUUUCACAAUCAAAAUUAGGUGCCUGUUUCUUAAAAUUAGAUUCUGCUGCAGGUUUACAUACUAGACUUUUCAGCCUGCAUGAAUUAGUAGGGAUAUUCUUUUUUUACUUGCAUAAUUGUAAUUGAUUUAAACAUGUAUGCCAGAAUUCACAGGCCCAUACUAACUGUCCUUAAUUUCUUUCCUACAGCAGUACUGCUAUAUGCCAGUCCUGUCUGCAUUCUUAAGGGUGCAGUUCAACACAUCCUCUCUAGAUUAUGGUGAAAAAGUAUUCCAAAGGAAGUCUUAUCAGAGCUAGUGUCAGAAAGAAUGACACUACCAAUUGGGCAUGAUCUUCAGCAUAGGAAAUGUCUUAGAAUUUUAUUAUUUUUUCCUAAAUUGUGAUGCUAUACUACUUGUAUAGCUAGUUACCACAUUUCUAAAGCAUAGUGUGCCUCUGUGAAUCUUGUUAUAUACUGUUUGGGCUUCUGUAAGAUAUUUUGAAGUUUGAAAAGCAAAUACUGAAACUUUAACCAAGAGACUGACACAUCUCUUUGUACACCACGUUGCUUCUGUGUGCAUCAUAAUAACUGGUAGAAGUAAUAUAUUUAAAGUAAUAUGUUUCCAGUUUUAAUUUAUGCUUUCUAAGAAAUAAAAAUAUGUUUUCUGGGUCAACAAAACUUAAAGCAUGAAGCCCUUUUUAGUAACGUGACAUCAGAAUAAGAUUAUAGGUAUAUUUUUAAAAUCAGAUUUUCUAAACUACAAUUGUUUUAGAACACUGUAUGAAGAACUUAUCUAGUCAUAGUUAUUUGUAGUCAGGAUUUUAACAGCUUGCAACAGGUAAUGUUUUGAAUAUAAAUAUCUUUCCAAAGUGUUACUAAUGGUAAAGAGAUAAUUUUCUAGGCUUCUAUUCUGCUGCUUGAAGUCAGAACUGCUGAUGGAGACAAAGGCACGAAAGUGUACGUAUUCCGGAUUAGCAACCCAGGAACCCAUCACUUCUGAAGACUCUAAACUGUGCUGUCAUUUUGUUUUUAUAUGCAUUAAAAUAUUUGUUUUAAACUGCUGUAGAUGUUUGUGUUCAAACAGGUUAAAUUGAUCAGCAAACUCAAUAAAAAGUAAGAUGUAUAAUUAUUAAAGUUUUCCAUCAAAAAAUAAUUUAAAUGAUUAUGGAAUAACAUAAUAUUUAGAGCAGGGCAGAUAAAUCAGUUGAACCUGCUUAUUUUUUAUUUAUUGUACUCUUUUUCCUGUUGCUGUUCUUUUCUGCAGGAGGGAAAACCCCUGAUCCUAAAAUGAAUGCUAGGACUUACAUGGAUGUAAUGCGAGAACAACACUUGACUAAAGAAGAACGAGAAAUUAGGCAACAGCUAGCAGAAAAAGCUAAAGCUGGAGAACUAAAAGUCGUCAAUGGAGCAGCAGCGUCCCAGCCUCCAUCAAAACGAAAACGGCGUUGGGAUCAAACAGCUGAUCAGACUCCUGGUGCCACUCCCAAAAAACUAUCAAGUUGGGAUCAGGCAGAGACCCCUGGGCAUACUCCUUCCUUAAGAUGGGAUGAGACACCAGGUCGUGCAAAGGGAAGCGAGACUCCUGGAGCAACCCCAGGCUCAAAAAUAUGGGAUCCUACACCUAGCCACACACCAGCGGGAGCUGCUACUCCUGGACGAGGUGAUACACCAGGCCAUGCGACACCAGGCCAUGGAGGCGCAACUUCCAGUGCUCGUAAAAACAGAUGGGAUGAAACCCCCAAAACAGAGAGAGAUACUCCUGGGCAUGGAAGUGGAUGGGCUGAGACUCCUCGAACAGAUCGAGGUGGAGAUUCUAUUGGUGAAACACCGACUCCUGGAGCCAGUAAAAGAAAAUCACGGUGGGAUGAAACACCAGCUAGUCAGAUGGGUGGAAGCACUCCAGUUCUGACCCCUGGAAAGACACCAAUUGGCACACCAGCCAUGAACAUGGCUACCCCUACUCCAGGUCACAUAAUGAGUAUGACUCCUGAACAGCUUCAGGCUUGGCGGUGGGAAAGAGAAAUUGAUGAGAGAAAUCGCCCACUUUCUGAUGAGGAAUUAGAUGCUAUGUUCCCAGAAGGAUAUAAGGUACUUCCUCCUCCAGCUGGUUAUGUUCCUAUUCGAACUCCAGCUCGAAAGCUGACAGCUACUCCAACACCUUUGGGUGGUAUGACUGGUUUCCACAUGCAAACUGAAGAUCGAACUAUGAAAAGUGUUAAUGACCAGCCAUCUGGAAAUCUUCCAUUUUUAAAACCUGAUGAUAUUCAAUACUUUGAUAAACUAUUGGUUGAUGUUGAUGAAUCAACACUUAGUCCAGAAGAGCAAAAAGAGAGAAAAAUAAUGAAGUUGCUUUUAAAAAUUAAGAAUGGAACACCACCAAUGAGAAAGGCUGCAUUGCGUCAGAUUACUGAUAAAGCUCGUGAAUUUGGAGCUGGUCCUUUGUUUAAUCAGAUUCUUCCUCUGCUGAUGUCUCCUACACUUGAGGAUCAAGAGCGUCAUUUACUUGUGAAAGUUAUUGAUAGGAUACUGUACAAACUUGAUGACUUAGUUCGUCCAUAUGUGCAUAAGAUCCUCGUGGUCAUUGAACCGCUAUUGAUUGAUGAAGAUUACUAUGCUAGAGUGGAAGGCCGAGAGAUCAUUUCUAAUUUGGCAAAGGCUGCUGGUCUGGCUACUAUGAUCUCUACCAUGAGACCUGAUAUAGAUAACAUGGAUGAGUAUGUCCGUAACACAACAGCUAGAGCUUUUGCUGUUGUAGCCUCUGCCCUGGGCAUUCCUUCUUUAUUGCCCUUCUUAAAAGCUGUGUGCAAAAGCAAGAAGUCCUGGCAAGCGAGACACACUGGUAUUAAGAUUGUACAACAGAUAGCUAUUCUUAUGGGCUGUGCCAUCUUGCCACAUCUUAGAAGUUUAGUUGAAAUCAUUGAACAUGGUCUUGUGGAUGAGCAGCAGAAAGUUCGGACCAUCAGUGCUUUGGCCAUUGCUGCCUUGGCUGAAGCAGCAACUCCUUAUGGUAUCGAAUCUUUUGAUUCUGUGUUAAAGCCUUUAUGGAAGGGUAUCCGCCAACACAGAGGAAAGGGUUUGGCUGCUUUCUUGAAGGCUAUUGGGUAUCUUAUUCCUCUUAUGGAUGCAGAAUAUGCCAACUACUAUACUAGAGAAGUGAUGUUAAUCCUUAUUCGAGAAUUCCAGUCUCCUGAUGAGGAAAUGAAAAAAAUUGUGCUGAAGGUGGUAAAACAGUGUUGUGGGACAGAUGGUGUAGAAGCAAACUACAUUAAAACAGAGAUUCUUCCUCCCUUUUUUAAACACUUCUGGCAGCACAGGAUGGCUUUGGAUAGAAGAAAUUACCGACAGUUAGUUGAUACUACUGUGGAGUUGGCAAACAAAGUAGGUGCAGCAGAAAUUAUAUCCAGGAUUGUGGAUGAUCUGAAAGAUGAAGCCGAACAGUACAGAAAAAUGGUGAUGGAGACAAUUGAGAAAAUUAUGGGUAAUUUGGGAGCAGCAGAUAUUGAUCAUAAACUUGAAGAACAACUGAUUGAUGGUAUUCUUUAUGCUUUCCAAGAACAGACUACAGAGGACUCAGUAAUGUUGAACGGCUUUGGCACAGUGGUUAAUGCUCUUGGCAAACGAGUCAAACCAUACUUGCCUCAGAUCUGUGGUACAGUUUUGUGGCGUUUAAAUAACAAAUCUGCUAAAGUUAGGCAACAGGCAGCUGACUUGAUUUCUCGAACUGCUGUUGUCAUGAAGACUUGUCAAGAGGAAAAAUUGAUGGGACACUUGGGUGUUGUAUUGUAUGAGUAUUUGGGUGAAGAGUACCCUGAAGUAUUGGGCAGCAUUCUUGGAGCACUGAAGGCCAUUGUAAAUGUCAUAGGUAUGCAUAAGAUGACUCCACCAAUUAAAGAUCUGCUGCCUAGACUCACCCCCAUCUUAAAGAACAGACAUGAAAAAGUACAAGAGAAUUGUAUUGAUCUUGUUGGUCGUAUUGCUGACAGGGGAGCUGAAUAUGUAUCUGCAAGAGAGUGGAUGAGGAUUUGCUUUGAGCUUUUAGAGCUCUUAAAAGCCCACAAAAAGGCUAUUCGUAGAGCCACAGUCAACACAUUUGGUUAUAUUGCAAAGGCCAUUGGCCCUCAUGAUGUAUUGGCUACACUUCUGAACAACCUCAAAGUUCAAGAAAGGCAGAACAGAGUUUGUACCACUGUAGCAAUAGCUAUUGUUGCAGAAACAUGUUCACCCUUUACAGUACUCCCUGCCUUAAUGAAUGAAUACAGAGUUCCUGAACUGAAUGUUCAAAAUGGAGUGUUAAAAUCGCUUUCCUUCUUGUUUGAAUAUAUUGGUGAAAUGGGAAAAGACUACAUUUAUGCCGUAACACCGUUACUUGAAGAUGCUUUAAUGGAUAGAGACCUUGUACACAGACAGACGGCUAGUGCAGUGGUACAGCACAUGUCACUUGGGGUUUAUGGAUUUGGUUGUGAAGAUUCGCUGAAUCACUUGUUGAACUAUGUAUGGCCCAAUGUAUUUGAGACAUCUCCUCAUGUAAUUCAGGCAGUUAUGGGAGCCCUAGAGGGCCUGAGAGUUGCUAUUGGACCAUGUAGAAUGUUGCAAUAUUGUUUACAGGGUCUGUUUCACCCAGCCCGGAAAGUCAGAGAUGUAUAUUGGAAAAUUUACAACUCCAUCUACAUUGGUUCCCAGGACGCUCUCAUAGCACAUUACCCAAGAAUCUACAACGAUGAUAAGAACACCUAUAUUCGUUAUGAACUUGACUAUAUCUUAUAAUUUUAUUGUUUAUUUUGUGUUUAAUGCACAGCUACUUCACACCUUAAACUUGCUUUGAUUUGGUGAUGUAAACUUUUAAACAUUGCAGAUCAGUGUAGAACUGGUCAUAGAGGAAGAGCUAGAAAUCCAGUAGCAUGAUUUUUAAAUAACCUGUCUUUGUUUUUGAUGUUAAACAGUAAAUGCCAGUAGUGACCAAGAACACAGUGAUUAUAUACACUAUACUGGAGGGAUUUCAUUUUUAAUUCAUCUUUAUGAAGAUUUAGAACUCAUUCCUUGUGUUUAAAGGGAAUGUUUAAUUGAGAAAUAAACAUUUGUGUACAAAAUGCUAAUUUGUGUGUGUUUUUUGAACAUGACUUGUAAAAUGCGGAACUUUGAUAAAGUAUUGGUUUAUGUGGAAUAAGUGGCUUAAUUUCAUUUUCUGUCACAUGGUUUAUAGAAAGUAGUUAGCUGAAUAAAAACUAUAUAAAGUGAUGGCAUCUUUGUCAAAAUUCCAUUGUUGUGUUAAUAAUGACAGCAAGAAGAGUAGCCUCAGGGGAUGUUCCCCUCAAACUAGCACAACCAUUCCAUCAUCGUAGAAAAGUAGCACUUUUGCUAAACUGUCUUGAAUAUUUUGUACUUACAUAGCGCCUUUCAUCUCUUGAUUUCUCAAAAUGCUUUAUGAACACAUUUAAAGAAAGUGGUUUAAGUCUUGUCCAACACUUGACAGGUCUGCUGUGUUUAGCAAGUGAGGAAUUUAACUUUACUUCAAAACUGCUUUCUGCCUAUUAGGAGUGAGGAUACCUAAGUAAUGCUGAUAGAACAGGACAAUGUUGGGCUUUUCUCCAUGUUAUAAGCCACUACUCAGCAAUGCAUCAGUAAAUACCUAUUCACCCACUGUAUGCCAGCCACUGUGCUUAUAUGCAGGGGAUGCAAAGGUGCAUGAGACCUGCCCUCUACCUUUAAGAACAGUAUAAUGGAGAAGGGGAGACAAACCUUGUGACAGAUUCCUUAUGUACUGUGAUAAUACACAGUGGCAGCAGCUAAAAUGUCUAGGUUUGCUUAGCUUUGUAUUCAGUAAUAAUAAGUUGAUCUAAGAGUUCAGCAUAAACUGAAUGAAAUGCCAUUUAAUGGUAGAGGAACCAAGCAUUAAGGCAGUACUACACUUAAUUUUUUAAGCAAAUAUGUAAAGUAUAUUUUCAAACUUUUCUAAUGUUAUGGCCCCAAAUUUCUUAGUUUUGGCCUUUUUACUACCUAUACUAUUUUUACUGUUUUGUUUUGUCUCCAUGUGGUAGUACUUCUGUGAACUCUAAAGGGAAAAAAAAUUCUGCAAGCAGCAUUAGUAUAUAACUACUACUGUAAGUAAAACUGCCUAUUGACACUUUAGGAGUUCCUGCUUCAGAAGCUUAGUUAAGAAACAGCUUGUGGCCGGGUGUGGUGGCUCAUGCCUGUAAUCCCAGCACUUUGGGAGGCUGAGGCGGGCGGAUCACGAGGUCAGGAGAUCGAGACCAUCCUGGCUAACGCGGUGAAGUCCCGUCUACUAAAAAUACAAAAAUUAGCCAGGCGUGGUGGCGGGCGCCUGUAGUCCCAGCUACUAGGGAGGCUGAGGCAGGAGAAUGGCUUGAACCCGGGAGGCGGAGCUUGCAGUGAGCCGAGAUAGCGCUGCUACACUCCAGCCUGGGCGACAGAGACUCCGUCUCAAAAAAAAAAAAAAAAUUGACUUUCAACAAAUUGAUAGUGAGCAUUAAGGGUUUCCAAGUUGGAUUUGUAACUCCUCAUCAUUCCUUGUAUGACAACUUUCUGAAUAUAUGUCACUAUGUAGUAAAAUUAAACACUCCAAACUCAUCUUUCUGUUGUUAGAAGUUUUCAGCGGUACUUCCAUGCAACUUUAAAUCUCACUGCUCUCUAUGGUUGAUGUCAAAUGACCUUCAGUAAUGACUGAGAAUUGAAUACAAAUAGAUUACAAAGCCAAAAUUUGAUGUUAAAUGACUCAGGAAAUUUUAGUUGUAUUUUCAAUUCAAGUACUUAGUAGCCUACGUUUGCUUGGCCUCUGGUUCUUUAUGGAAAAUAGGCUUUGUAGUGGCAUUGUGGAGCAAAGGAGACUGUUACACCUUAAUUAACUUUUUUUACUGAUGCAAAUAAUUUGAGGAUAGAGAGGAGGGAAGUAGUGAAAGCUAUGACCUAAAACAUUGGGACCAAAUAGAGGCUCACAGAUAUUUGGAUUAUUUUAUGUGCUUAUUAUUAAAUAAGGAAAGCAUUUUGUGAUAUGUGGAAGACGCUAUGUGAAGUUUUACCUAUCUUCUCAAAGACCUUUUCUUUUGUAUUUUCUUUUGGUGUUUCUUAAAGCCAAACAAAGAAAUGUUCUUAAGGAGACAGGGUGGGUUUUUCUGUGGGCCUUUGUUGGUUUUUCUGUGGGCCAUCGCCCUCUAAUGGAAUUGAUCUCUGGCUGUUUGAUUUUUUUCAUAUUGUAUUUUUAAAAUUUGUUGUACAGUGCCCUGUGAGCACCAAGUACCACUAGAUGAAUAAAACGUAUUAUAUCUAAA